GCUCCCUCCCCUCCUAGCUGGCUUCGGCGGGGACGGCGGCGGCGGCGGCGGGCGGGGAGGGCGUGCGCCGGCCGAGAGGUGUCGGCGGCGAGGCAAAGGAAGUUUCAAGUGGAAGGUCGUCCGUCGGCCGGCGCGUCCUCCUGCUCUCCUCCGCAGCAUCAUGGCGGAGCCGAGCGGCUCGCCCGUGCACGUCCAGCUUCCCCAGCAGGCGGCCCCGGUGACAGCGGCGGCGGCGGCGGCCCCGGCGGCCGCGACAGCAGCGCCGGCCCCGGCAGCUCCCGCGGCCCCGGCCCCGGCCCCGGCCCCGGCGGCACAGGCUGUCGGCUGGCCCAUCUGCAGGGACGCGUACGAGCUGCAGGAGGUUAUCGGCAGUGGAGCUACUGCUGUGGUUCAGGCAGCCCUAUGCAAACCCAGGCAAGAACGUGUAGCAAUAAAACGGAUCAACUUGGAAAAAUGCCAGACCAGUAUGGAUGAACUAUUAAAAGAAAUUCAAGCCAUGAGUCAGUGCAGCCAUCCCAACGUAGUGACCUAUUACACCUCUUUUGUGGUCAAAGAUGAACUUUGGCUGGUCAUGAAAUUACUAAGUGGAGGUUCAAUGUUGGAUAUCAUAAAAUACAUUGUCAACCGAGGAGAACACAAGAAUGGAGUUCUGGAAGAGGCAAUAAUAGCAACAAUUCUUAAAGAGGUUUUGGAAGGCUUAGACUAUCUACACAGAAACGGUCAGAUUCACAGGGAUUUGAAAGCUGGUAAUAUUCUUCUGGGUGAGGAUGGUUCAGUACAAAUAGCAGAUUUUGGGGUAAGUGCGUUCCUAGCAACAGGGGGUGAUGUUACCCGAAAUAAAGUAAGAAAAACAUUCGUUGGCACCCCAUGUUGGAUGGCUCCUGAAGUCAUGGAACAGGUGAGAGGCUAUGACUUCAAGGCUGACAUGUGGAGUUUUGGAAUAACUGCCAUUGAAUUAGCAACAGGAGCAGCGCCUUAUCACAAAUAUCCUCCCAUGAAAGUGUUAAUGUUGACUUUGCAAAAUGAUCCACCCACUUUGGAAACAGGGGUAGAGGAUAAAGAAAUGAUGAAAAAGUACGGCAAGUCCUUUAGAAAAUUACUUUCACUGUGUCUUCAGAAAGAUCCUUCCAAAAGGCCCACAGCAGCAGAACUUUUAAAAUGCAAAUUCUUCCAGAAAGCCAAGAACAGAGAGUACCUGAUUGAGAAGCUGCUUACAAGAACACCAGACAUAGCCCAAAGAGCCAAAAAGGUAAGAAGAGUUCCUGGGUCAAGUGGUCACCUUCAUAAAACCGAAGACGGGGACUGGGAGUGGAGUGACGACGAGAUGGAUGAGAAGAGCGAAGAAGGGAAAGCAGCUUUUUCUCAGGAAAAGUCACGAAGAGUAAAAGAAGAAAAUCCAGAGAUUGCAGUGAGUGCCAGCACCAUCCCCGAACAAAUACAGUCCCUCUCUGUGCACGACUCUCAGGGCCCACCCAAUGCUAAUGAAGACUACAGAGAAGCUUCUUCUUGUGCCGUGAACCUCGUUUUGAGAUUAAGAUGGACUUGAUCACGUCUACCUAAUUAAAUGUCCUGUUAGACAUUCUGCCGAAGUUUAAAAAGGUACAGUUUGUAUAUAUUUUUACUUAUGUUAUUUUUGUUAGAGAAAGGGAAGGAAAAACUAAAAUAAGAUAAAAUUCUUUGAUUUGCUUUUAAUAACUACCCUUUGGGAUAUUUUAGAAUUGAAGUAGUAGCUAUAUAUUUGUUUUUAAUUAUUAUUCUAAAAUUGAAAGGAACUUGUAAGCAAGCAUGUUGGUGAUGACGUGUCAGGUGCUGAAGUGAAAUUGAAUCAUCUUUUAUGUCCCAAGCAAAGCAAGAGCACCAUCACAAACAUCCUUAUUUCCAUCUUUUAAAACCCCUCAAAGGCAGAAAUCUUUUUUCAUUCAUAACCAGUCAAAAGCAUGAACAACCCUUCUGGAUACAGGAGGUUCCCAGGCCAACCUCAAAUCAUUAACGACCAACUUUGAUAUUGGUUCCAAGUCUUUCAAAUACAUGGCGGUUUGGCAGUCAGAUACAAGCUCUAUUUUUGUAAAAAGCCUUUUCACUUCUCUGUUCAGGUCAUUUUUAAAUGUUUUAUUAAUGACCACAUCAACAGGCUGAAGGAGGUCACUAUUGCUGAGAUGCAGAUAAAAAUGAGUAUUAUGGUUUUUUUCUCCCAGUUGGCUCAGUGGGAAAUCCUAUUAGUGCUCUAAGAAGUUAUAUAAUUAGCAUGGCACCCGCUGCUCGUUUGUUGAGCCAAACUGGUUUUUAAUGUUCAGAAUACAAAACAUGGCAGGGCCAUCUUCAUAAUGCUCUGUGCUGUCACUGGUUGCCAGGAGCGUUUCUGCGUGACCGAUCCAUAAUAACAGCAAUGAUGAGAGCCACAAUUAAAUAGCACCCUGUGUUUGGAGCACUGGUCCUUCAGGUAUCCCUUAGUCCAGUGAGUUCCUGAAUGCUGGAGAGUGUGUAACAUCAGUGCCAUGUGUGCUCUGUCUUCUGGUGCAGAGGAAGAGAGUUACCAGCAAUGGUGGCCAGCCACUGGCAAAAUGGGUGCUUUUCUUCCAUCCCUUUUUUCGUCAGAGACUUCCUCUGAUUUGACAGGAUCACACACUUUAAGCAUGUUUCAGUCUUCUAUAUCUUCUAACUUCACAUGAACUUGGCUCUUUGAUUUCACCAAACAAAGCCAUUACUUUAAAUUUAUUUAUAAGGGCAACAAUUAUUAGCUGGAUUAUCAGAAAACUUCUCAGAUUCUCAUGGGCUUGUUUCACUCCCUGACAAUUAUCAAGGUAAGUCAAUCCCAGUCUCUUUGUUUCAAACCCCAAGCCAGAGUGUCAGUCUCCACCUCCACAUGGUCAGGGCCUGUUUACUCAAGCAAUGCUGGGCCGCUUGAGGACAUGCAGGGGCCUGCCUCCCCCAAAUCUUGUUAUGUAUGUUGGGUUCAUUGUUAGCAGCUGCUGUAGGACUCAGUGGAGGAUUUGAUACCUACACUCUUGUUUAGGAUAGGUGAAGGGAUGAGACAGAAAAGAUCUCAGGGCAGGGACUAAGAUUGGACUUGUAAAACACAACACCUAAAGAUUAUACAUAUUGCUGUUGAUGUUUUUUCACUAAUACUGAGUGCUUGCAGAAGGCACUGUCCAUGCCUUCUCCUCAUAGUUAUGCCAUGAAGUAGUUCGUGUCACUACCUUAUUUUAUAGAUGAAGAGAGAAAGACUUGGAAAGUUAAGUAAAUUGCCCCAAGGUCUCAUAGCUCGUCAGUGUUACAAUCCGUAUUUAAACUCCAGAAUGUUAUCUCCAGAAACCAAGGUAGGACAGGCUGAGUCGGCCUAAGCAACCAAGUACUUUGUGCUCUCCUUUGACUCCUCUUGAUGAAAGGAUAGGAAAGGAGUCAGAAAAGAGGCUGUUACAAGGAGUUAUGCUCCCCUGCCUUCUCUGUUCAAAUAAAAUAAGUGUAUUGUACACUUCAGAACAGCCUGAAACUCAGUGCACAGGUGGCUCAGGAACAGCGUUUUAGAGCCAUAAAUGUAAAGCUUUUGUAGCCAUCCAGAGCUCUGCUACAUAUACCAAGGCCAGAGUAGGCCACAGCUUCUAUAUAUUGAGUCUUGUCUGAGCUGAACCCACCAUCCCAAAUGUUGACUGUUGGCUCACUGCUCAGGAGGAAUAGUUUCGUAGCCGGAAGUCUCUUCAAUGGAACAGAGCCCUUUACCUUUCUUAGAUUUUGUCCUAAUGCGAUAUUUCCUCUAUUGAGCAUAGCUCUGACCUGCAAAGCACCUCAAAUGCUCUCAGCCCAGAAACUCUUUUUUUUUUUUCUUUUUGCUGGUGUUACUUGAGUGUUUAUUAAGGGUUAAGGUUGCUGACUUCCGUACCUAGAAAUGUUGUCAAGUAUACUUACAUUUAAUAUACUGCCAUGCAUCAGGUAAGGACGACUAUUGUAUCCCUUGAUUCAGUUCAACUUCAUGAAUAUUUAUUGGGAAUGUACUUAUGUUGGCAGACCUGUGCCAGGUUCUUUAGGGGAGAGAGACUACCCAACAUCUUAGCUCCUCUGACCCAUCUCUUGAAUUCUGUGUAUUUGCCAAAAAGGCUUAUAACUGUUAACCUUUACCAUCCUUUUAUUUUUCAAAUGAACAUUCAGCAACUCGACUUCUUCUUAAACCAAGUAAUUUUCUUAAAUUAAAGUUGACAGAGAAUCAAUGGUUAUUUUAUUUUGCCUCAGACAUAGAGGAAAGCUCUCCUAUAUGUUACCCAUCGGGGAAAGGGCCCUCUUAUCUUUUCCUUCAGAGCUUCUUUCCUCUCUCCAGUCGCAGGGGCACUGUUUUUUAGGUUUUUGUUUUGCUUUGUUUUUUUGUACCUCCUUUCUGAAAAGCACGUCUGUCACUUUACUGUGAAGAGGCAAAUAGCAGGUUGUUUGCAGGAUGCACUGUAUAUACACUUCUGAAGAGUGAGAACUUGUCUUUGUCCAGCCUGACAUCCUUUAUUAAAUUUUUACUCAAGAGGUCAGGAAAGAUAAGCUAGUCUUAAAAACUUGUCAGAAGUCAACGGUUUAGGUAAAGGACAGUCAUUGAAGAAACCAUUAUGAAGGAAAUUGUUGGGUGUAUCUUUUUCAUUAGUUAUUCUUAGGUAUGGAAAACACAUUACCCCCACAGUCUUGUUAAGUCCUUAACUUGGUGGUACAGUUACACCCCUGGGUGUUGCUUAUUCAACAUUCUCAAAGAACAAGUUUUUCAAAUCAUCCAAAUGUGAGUUAUGGCUCUAAUCAUACAGAUUCCAUGACUCAUACACAAAAAUCAGCUUUAUUAUUUGAUAAUCACACGGCAUGUGUUUAAACACUGAGGAAAAUGUUUUGAGCGUUUGAAAUACGAUUACAUAUUAUACCAGUCUGCUUUUAAGUCUUGUCCUUGGAUAUAUCCUUCAUGGUGGAGUUGACAUUGCACCAUUGAAGACUAUAUUUCAUGAAUAAGCACAAGGGUUUUUCUACUUUUGGCAAACUUCAGGUGCUUGGAAAUUUCCAAUUAGGGUGGCUGGUAUCUAUGCCAAGUGAUUGAUUUCAUUUUAUUUACUUUAUUUGGAACCGUUGAAGGGAUGAUGUCUUCCCAAACCAUUGUAAUAAUGAGUGGUAUAAGUUAGUGUUCCAGAGGCCGAGAACAAAUUUAGUUUUUACCAAAGGGACAAAUGUUGACUUUUAAAUAUUUGUCAGAAUCAGAUAGUAUAUUAGUUUGCUAGGGCUGCCUUAACAAAGAACCACAAACUGGGUCGCUUAAACAAUAGGAGUUUAUUUUCUCAUUGUUCUGGCGCCUAGAAGUCUACGAUGAAGCUGCCCAAAGGUUUAGCUUCUCCUGAAGUCUCUCUCUAUGGCUUGUAGAAGACCUUCUUGCUGUUCUUAUGUGAUCUUUCCUCUGUGCGGGCACAUGUCUGUGUCCUAAUCUCUUCUUAUAACGACACCUGUCCUGUUGGAUUAGGGCCCACCCUAAUGAUCUCACUUAACUUUAAUUACCUCUUUGAAGACCCUGUCCCCAAAUACGGUCACAUUCUGAGGUACUGGCUGUUAGGCUUUCAACAUGAAUCUGAACUGUGUGUUCAGCCCAUAAGAAAUGAGAAGGGAAAAGGCUUCAUGUGGUGGCCACUUCUCAGGGCCACUCUGUGUUAAUAAGAGUUGUGUGGGCAGAACAGCAGUGGGGCUUAAGAAGGGGCAUCCCUGGGAAGCAGAUAAGGCUGAGCUUCAGAUUUCCCUUCUCUUACUUGAGGGAAUCUUCAGAUUUAAAAAGAAAAUAGAUUUUGUAAAAAACUGACCUGGAAACAGUGUCAGGUAUUUGUCGUCUCUUUAAAUACUGUCAUGCAAAUCAUACCCCUUCUGGUACCCUUGCCCUUCUGGGAGAUGUCACCCUAAAAGGGGCUUUCCAAGCUCUGCUCUCAGCUUUCAGGCACCCACUCCGCUCUUCUCCAGGGCAGGCCAGAGGAGUUUCAGUCCUGUGAGUGUUAGUCAUUGGAGAACCAUGUAACCCCAACCUCCAAAAACAAGCAGAUGCAUUUUUUCUUUCUUUUUGCCUUGAGAGAAUCUUUGGAUUUUUGGUUUGUUUAGACAUUCUGCAUGAAAAGUCCUGUCCUCAUCCGGUCUCCUGGCAAGUGUGCCCUGAUGUAUUCUCGUGCAUGGAUGUUUCCUUCUGAUAUACAUUAACAACCUAGCAAAUGCCUAGGAACAAUGUUACUUUCUGUGCAACUAUGUAUUUUAUAAAUAAUCAUUUGCUGAAGUAAUUUCAGAAAAGUUGAACUUGAGGAUUUAUAGUGGCUCUGCCCAAGGGUCAUUCAUCCUAGACUGUAAAUGCAGUUACUUACAGGCCUUUUACCUGAAGUGGAUCAAAAGGGGAAAUACUUGCUCCAUCUCAUUCAUCAUCAAAUUUAAUUAUCUUGCAGUACCACCUGUGGAAAAGUCAGGGGGAUUCUGCUUACAUUUCUACCCUGGAGGACACUGGCGUUAACACUUCUUAUUAAUUAGUUCUUCACAGUUUUUUCCUUUGAUGAGUGAUCAUUUUCCUUUUAAAUUUGCUAAUCUUUAAUAUAAUUUCCCCUGGAUUCGAUUACACAUAUACAUUAAUAGUAAAAUUACAGGAAUAGGAAAAUUAAAGUAUGUUUCUAUUUCUGUGAUUUCUUGGCUAAAGUUUAAAGAAUGUAUUGUCUGCUCACUUUAUAUUUUUUGUGAUUUAUGCUGGUUCUCUAUGGCUAACUCACUUGAUUAAUCACACACAUCUUUAAAACUUUUAAGCAAAAAAAAUUACUUCUUCCCUAUUCUGAAGCAACAAAAUUGGGAGAUUAUUAUUAUUAUUUUGAGACAGAGUCUCGCUCUGUCACACAGGCUAGAGUGCAGUGGCUGGAUUUCGGCUCACUGAAAGCUCCGCCUCCCAGAUUCAUGCCAUUCUCCUGCCUCAGCCUUCCGAGUAGCUGGACUACCGGCGCCCGCCACCACACCUGGCUAAUUUUUUGUAUUUUUUAGUAGAGACGGGGUUUCACCGUGUUAGCCAGGAUGGUCUCUAUCUCCUGACCUCGUGAUCCGCCCACCUCGGCCUCCCAAAGUGCUUGGAUUACAGGCAUGAGCCACCGCACCCGGCCCAAAAUUGGGAGAUUUAGCUGAGUACAUGUCCAAGGUGUUGGCCAGACACAGAACUUCCUUUGGAAGUUGCCACAUCCAGCAACCCACUCUCUUAGGUGUUAGCCACCAGCUUUCCAAGAGAGGACAUAAGCCAGUCUCCUGCAUGUUCAUGGCAGAAUGUUACUUCUGCUUCCUACAGAUGGUUUAGCUAAGGGGAAAGAUCUAUGUCUAAUCAGUACAUAGACUUUCAGACCCCUUCAAAUACCCGUCGGAGAAAGCAGUCAUGAAAUCGCCCUUUGUAGCACUUGACAAGACACUUUUGGGGCCUCAGGAAGAAGUGUGUAUAGGCGAUCCAUUUCUCCAGGUUCUUUGAGCUCCCUCUGUUGAGGUAAAUCAUCAGUAAACAAUGUGCUUCUGAUGUAUUAUUUCAGCUCCCAGCAGAAAUGCCAUCACUCAGGCAAGAUUUAAUAUUGUGUCUUCAGCACCUGGGAGAAAAAAACUUUCAUCGUUUGCACCAUAUGGUUGAAGACAUUUAUAUGAAAAAGGCUUCUGUCUUUUGUAACAUAAGUUGAAGACAUUACUCAGUGUCCCUUAUAAAGGGUCUUCCAUAAUAAAAUUUUCCCUGAAAUUAAUGCCAAGAUAAACAAAAUCUGCCUUGCAUGUUUCUCUUUUGAUGAAGUUAGAACUAUACUAUGCAACAGUUUCCCUUUUCUGCCUUAGUUUCAGGCAAGUAAAGCUAAAUCCGGUGCUCAGUUGGAGUAACUGACAUCUCAAGUAUGUACUAAUGUCUCUUUCUGCAUUCCUUUUAAUUAAUGUCUGUUAUUUUUAACAACAAAAUGUUCAGUUAUAUAUUUAGUUUAAUUUUGAAACUAUUUAACAUCCUUCUUGCAAGAAUUAAACCAAAUAACUAGUUGGCAAAAACCAUAAUUGUCCUUAAUAGUUAGAGUUUGUAACAGUUUGUGCCUUAAAGAUAUAAACUUCUAUUGUCUUAAAAAUGCAUUUAUCUCAGAAUGUACCAAUGUGUGCAGCUCCACCCACCUCGCCAUAUACUGUUCAGUUUGUAUAAAUACACCUACUAAGACAUGAUGUCUGGGUCCCAAAUGGACACAUAUUAGGUUCAUGUCUUAUAGAUGCCUUUACAUUCCUGUUAGAAAGUACUUAGCGUGUUGGUUUGGGAGCCUCAUGCAUGGGAGAGAGGUAUACAUCACAGAGACAAUGAUGAGUCUGUGAGUUCUCUGCAGUAAAACCCACCACACCCUAAACUUAAAGGCACAAAUAAUGUUAAUGAAGGCUGGUCCUGUAUCAGUUGAUUGAAAAGAACAGUGAUCUACAGAGAUCCUUACAUAGUGAGCAUGAUUAACAUUUUUUCCUGCUACAAAAAAGUGUGAACUUUGACCAGACUAUCAUGUUUCUGCUCCUACCUGCCAUUAACAUGAGUCUGGUAUUUAUAUGAUUACUCCUUUUCCCCUUUGCCCCAUAAGUGAAAAUAAGUUCAAUAAAUAUAUUCACUAGACAUCCUAAAUGCUGAAAAGGACUGCUUGCUACAUGUGACAUUAUAGUUCCAUAAUCUUGACAGGAAGCAGCACCCUUACACAAUGACCUGUUCUCUCCUGAUUUACUAUAGCUGGGAUGUAACACAAGUGACUUUGUGCUGUGUAGGUGAAACAUUCUUAAAAUUUUAUGUAUUCAGCUCUGAAGUAAAUAUGACAAAAUAUUACCAUUUUUAAAAUUCUGGAUGGUAGGCACAUGUGUAUUCAUUGUAUUACUCUUUGCACAUUCCUGUAUGUUGAAAUGUUUUUUAUAAUUUUUGAAACUAUUAUGUAAUAGAGAAAAAAAAAGAGUCCACCAUGGUUGUUUAGGUUGAAGAGUGGGUAAGGUUAGGGAGAGGAAACAGCCAUGCCCUUCACCUGGCAGGCAUGGAGAUUUUCCAGAGGUUUCUGUCAGAGAAAAUCACCUUAACUUAGUUUGGAUUACUUCUAGAUGAAAACUCUUUUUCGUAGCUAGGGAAGAAGUCUGUUAUUUAUAUUUCUGCAUGCGAUUUAUUCAUGUGUCAGCCCUGGACUGAGUAUUAGAGAUCUCUCCAUGAAAGGCUGACAUGUGUGCACUGCUAGUGUCGGUGUCAGCUGUGUGAAAUCCUAUGCAGCCAGACUGUUUGCUCCCUGCAGGCCGCAAACCUAAAAGGGUCCUUCAGGCUGUCAGGUAGCCAGCGGGAACUGUCAAGAGUCUCAAGCCUGAGGUUCCAGUUGCAGAAGAACCUGCAGUUAACCAGUGUGUGAGGCCAAAUUCUUUAAAAUAUGUUGAGAUAUCUUAUUUGAAGAAAACCUUGUGCGUAUUUGUGUAUGUGUGUGCUCAUGCACACACGUGUGCAUGUACGUGUGUGUACAUACAUGUGUAUGUGUACAUGCAUGUAUGUAUAUCACUUAGUCUCUGCUUUUGUUGUUGUUAAAGGGAACAGUGUGACUUUCUGAUCUAUCUGACAUUGGUUUGGGGCUGUGUGAUGCUGCAUGGCUUGAUGCAGACUAGAAUUCCAGAUGCUACUAACUACAUUUUCUAGGCCAGGGGCAUAUUUCUGCACGUGUGGAGGUGCACGCUGAAAGGAAUUUUCACUUUUUAGAAGACUCACUGAUCCAAAAGACACUUUUGCAGUAAGUUAAAUGUAAGGGCAAGGGUUUGGAGGGGAGGGGAAAGUAUGUGGUUCAGCUACUAUUCUCACAGCCUUGGAGCAUAUGGCCCAUGGUGGCUGGAGAUACACACAUCCAGGAGAGCUUCGAUUUCGGGCAAGGCUGUGGGCCACAGUGCUGAUAGGUUCAGCAGUGGUUCUCAACCUUUAGAGCCACAGAUAGAGGGCACAAACUGUUUCCUUUCCCCUACCUUACCCACCCUCCAACCUCAACAAACUCAGUGGUUCUUUUUUCCUCUAGUAUAUAAUACUUUCAAAAAUUAUAAAAAACAUUUCAACAUAUAGGAAUGUGCAAAGUAAUAAAUGCACAUGUAUCUACCAUCUAGAAUUUUGUGUGUGUGUGUGUAGAGACCAGAUCUCACGGUGUGUCCCAGGCUGGUCUCAAACUCCUGGGUUCAAGUGAUCUUCCCUCCUCAGCUUCUCAAAGUGCUGAGAUUACAGACGUGAGCCACUGGGCCUGACAUAGAAUGUGUUAAAUGGUAACAUUGUGUCAUAUUGACUACAGAGCUGAUUAUAUAAAUUUUAAUUUCUGCCAUCAUAUCAAUCAUGGAAGACACUUUCCCGUCUAUAGUGCCUCUCACUGCAUGCAGCAAUUCUUAACUGAGUGCAGGGGUAUAACUGGGGGAAAAGUCUUCCUUUUAGAGAUUGCACCUCCCCUCACCCUGCCUGCAGUUUGAGAGCCAUCAGUCUAGAAUAAAGAGCAGUGGUCUAGAGGUCCUGAGUCCCAGGUUCUGUUGUCAUUUCUUCCGUUAAUGGCUCCUGGCACAAACCUGACACAUAGUAGGUGAUCAAUAAUGAUUUAUGGAGAAUGGCAUGAAUUAACCAGCUGUGUUAUCUUAGACAAGCCACUUAAUCUCCUUGGCUUCAGUUUCUUCACCUAAAGAAUCAGAGAAAUGGAUUAGGUGACCUCUAAGGCCUCUUUCAGUUGUAAAAUUAUAUGAUUCUGUGAUUGGACCUUUACCUCGGAGGAAGAUUAAUUUGACAGGAGUGUGAAGGAUGGAUCAGAGUGAGAGCCAAGAGAGGGGAAUACACCUUUCUCUGAAUUAGUUCAAGAUUUCCUUCGCUACUAGUAUUUUUUAAGCACUUACUUACAUUGUUUUUCCCUGUAGUUUACAUAAACUGACCAUCAUUUUCUGCAAAGAUCGGAAACUUGUUAAUGACUGGAACUAUGACUUUUUCUCCCUAUUUCUAUGUGCCUCAAAAUAUGAGGCCUAAUAAUGGCUUAUAGCAGUAGCACAGAGUUCAUACAGUGUUUUCACACAGCUUGUUAAAUCUGCGAGGGAAGCAUUAUUUCCCCUUUUUACUGCAGAGGAAACCGAAUGUUGGAGAGGUGAAGUGGCUUACUGAAUGUCAUUGCUGGUAAGUGGAUUAACUCCAAAUUGGGCUCAGCUGACCAGUCUUCAAUUCCCGAAGGAGUCUCCAGUUCUGACGUGAAGACACUGCCAUAGGAAGGCCCCGGGAUGAGCAGGGAUACUGCUUCAGAGCAGCCGUCAGCUUGGCCACAGGAAGCUGCCCCUUUCACUUCGUGGCUCUUUUAUUUCUGGCCUUCAUUUGUAGGUUCCUUCUGUGUAUCCUCAUAUUGCCUAAUCUUUUCAUGUCUCAUUAAGUACAACAAUUUUCCCUGAGGGCUGCACAUUCGUCUGCCAAGGACUAUUCCCUGAAUAGCAGCUCCCUCAACCUUUUACAGCCCUUUUUCCUGCUGUUGUAUGUCUUUAGCCUUAGCAAAAGCCAUGUAUACGUGUGUAUAUGUGAGUGCAUGUGAAAUACUCUUUACUUAUUCAGUCAUUUCUUCUCAUCUGUGGUAGACGAUGGUGGCCUGACCUUGGUCAGUAGCAGUGAAGUUUGAGAGAAACGGAUGAUACGAGAACUCUUACAGAGGUAUAACCUACAGGUCUUGAUAGUGGGCCAUCACUAUCAUUUACUGCCAUAAGGAGCUAAGGAAGGGAAAUGUAUCUGAGAGGAAAAGUGAUACAUUCCGUUUUGGAGAUGCUGUGCCUUUUGGUGUCUUUUUGGACAUUGCAUUGAGAGAUACCAUAUAGGUAGUUGAUAAUGAAUUUUCAGCUCUGGGGCAGUACCUGAGAUUGAGUUAUGGAUUUGGAAUUAAUCAUCAAGGGAGAGAAUGAGAAGGGGAAAUGGUGAGGGAUGGAACAUUAACACUGAAGAGACAGCCAUACAGAGGUAGAGGAGUGUUUGGGGCACACAGAGAAAGGGCAGCUGGGGGACUGGAGGAGACCAGAAGGAGGUGGUAUUACAGAAGCCAGGGAGAGGCACUUUAUAAAAGCCAGACUUGUAAACUCUGCAUUCAUUCAUCUGUUCAACAAAUACUAUCUGUGUACCCAGUAGGCGGGUAAGGGAUGUGCACUGGUGAAGAUAAUGGGUAACAUUUUUUAAAGUUCCAGCUUUAGUUCAGCUCUGUUGUUCAGACUGUGAUUUUGGAUCUAUUCUUUAUCCUUUCUAAGCCUCAGUUUCCUUGUCUCUAAAAUAAUAGAGGAUAAGAGCAGUUCCUGCUUUAAGAGUUGCUUUGAGUUUGGACUGAGAUAACAUAUGUAAAACAUCAAGCAUGUCCCAGCAGAUAGGAAAUGCUGUUGUCUUAGUCCAUUCGUGCUGAUACAACAAAAUACCAUAGACUGGGUAAUUCGUAAUGACCAGCAAUGUAUUGGCUCUUGGUUCUGGAGGCUGGGAAGUCUAAGGUUGGGGGCUGCACCAUCUUAAUGUCUUCUUGCUGUGUCAUGCCAUGGCAGAAGUGCAAAGAGAGGGUGAGAGAGAGCAAAAGAUUAAACUCACAGCCUCAAGCGCUUUUAGAAUUGGCAUUAAUCCAUUUGUGAGGGUGGCGCCCUCAUGACCUAAACACCUCUCAUUAGGCCCUACCUCCCAACACAGUCACAUCAGGGAUGAAGUUUCCAGCACAUCCUUUUUGGGGGAGACAUUCAAACCAUAGCAGCUGUGAAUUAUUAUUUCCCCCUCUCACAGUUGAGGAAACAGGUUACAGAAGGCCAAAUAAGUAGUUUGUGGUUUUGAACUCAGAUCCCCAUCUGCAUGGGUCACAUUAUCUCCUCAUCCUGCCCCAGGCGGCCUCCUCGUGUGAAGCAGAAGUAUCUGCCCAGCUCACUGGGAGCCACAGUCCAUCCAUUUCUUCUCCUAAGACUGUGGGGAUGGACUUUGGUUUGGUGCCCAGAGUAGGACAAGAGGCAAGCUGAACUAAAAAUGAUGUCCUGACCAAUUCCUAGCUUAGCCUUUUUAAAAGGCCCCCUUCCUACUCCUGAUAGCGGGGAGAUAGUCCAGGAAUUGAGUGUGUGGGUAUCCCUUUGAAAUUCCCUGGACACUAACAGCUGCACCUUCACCUGGAAUUUCGGGUAAAAGUAAGGAAGAAGAGGGCUGUUGAUGAGAAAUCUUCUGCUGCUUAGGAGCGAGCAGCUGCUCCUGGGUCCCUGGGAAACACUAUCCCUGGCACUCUUACAGAGACCCUUGGUGGUGUUGCCAACCUCAAAGCUCGGGGAAAUAGUUGCCUUUCAUCUUCAUUUGAGAGCAUCCCUGCGGUGGAGGGUAUACAAUGCCAGUGACACUUACUGUUUCUGAUGCUCUUUGACAAUGAGUGGUCUUUGGAUUUCUACCGCUUUAAUCACAUCUGGGUCUUAGAGUGUGAGUGCCCUCAUACUGCUGCUGGCAUGGGCUAAGAGACGGUAAUGUGAGGCUGAAGGAUGCAAAUAGUUCUGAGCUGGCAUUUUGGCUUUGGAGCCCUCCAGGAGCAAUAACUCUGUCAGAUUGUCCUGACACGGUACAUUAAGAGGUGCAGAUAAAAGCUACAUCCUGUAAAAUAUAUACUUCAAUCGCACCUGCCUUCUGCACCUCCACCACUGGGAAGGGAUGGGUGUCCGUUCGUGUUCUGCAUUACCAGCCUCUUAGCCAGCUGCCUCGUUUGAUUGUUCGUUGUGUCACUUGAAGAUGAACUGAAAGAACAAGAAGAAAAACUUAAUGCACGCCAAUCUGUAUCUCUGAACUUCUCACGUUAAAUAGACAUAGCAAAAAAAAAAAAAAAAGUUUGUCAGCACUGAACAUCAAUUACUAAACAUUUUUUUAAAGUCAGGCUGGGCAUGGUGGCUCACACCUGUAAUCCCAGCACUUUGGAAUCCUGAGGUAGGGGGAAUCACUUGAGUCCAGAGUUCAACACCAGCCUCAGCAACAUAGCAAGACCCUUGUCUCUACAAAAAAUUAAAAAAUUAGCCAGGUAUGGGGGCACAUGCCCAUAGUUUAAGCUGCUCAGGAGGCUGAGGAAGGAGGAUUGCUUGAGCCCGAGAGUUCGAGGCUGCAGUGAGCAACAAGUGUGCCACUGUACUACCUGGGCAACCAAGUGAGACCUUGUCUCUAAAAGAAUCCAAAAAAUGAAAAAAACGAAUUUCAGUUUUAUAAGUUUAUGAAUUGUAUUUUCUUUUCGUUAGGUUUCUGUGGCUUUAUUUUUCUUUCCCAUGAUUAAUUUCUCCCAUGCCUUCAGUCUGUGGGUCUGUGUAUCAUUUAUUUGACUCUUUUUAGUAGAUCCUUAAAAAGAACUUUGAAGUUUACCAUUUCAGAAAACUUCAUCCCCAGAAAUCGGUUUAUUACUAUCAGCAGAAGUUAUAUUUUAUAUUUGCCCUCACUAAUGAAUGGUAAUAGACUGAAUCUGGCCCACACAUUAGUGUGAACAUUUUAAAAUUAGUAUCAACAAUUAAAACUAUGGAAUGUCAUAUAAAAUUUCAAAUUUCUUUUUUCUCUGACAAAUCUGAAUAUUGAGCAACAUUGAGUCCAAUCCUGUCUGGCCAUAACCUGCAGGCACUGAAUAGUGGUUGUCCCCUUUAGAUGGGGAAGAAGCUUUCCAGCUGGCACAGUCCCCACAUCUCCCUGGUUAUUAAUACAUUCUGAUUUAUUCAAAGUUCCUGCAAUAGUGCUUACAAAUGGUGGGUAAGAGCAUAAAUGGGUGCAACUUAAAUGAAGGGGAAUUUCAUAAUGUGUGUCAAAUUACAAAUGCAUAUAUCCUUUGACCAAAGAAUUCACCUCUAGACAUUUAUUUUUAUACUUGUAUUUAUGCAAAAUGACCUAAGAAUAAGGUUACUUAUUGAAGCACUGUUUACAAUAGUGAAAGAUUGGAAACAGUCUGUUCAUAGAAUGGGAACUGGUGAAAAAAGGCUGUAGCAUCCCAGAGAAAACUAUGUAGUUAUAAAGAAAAGAAUGAGAAAACUCUCUACAAACUAACAUGGAGAAAUUCCAAGAUGGUAUUAUGUUAAAAGAGAGGCAAGAUACAGAACAGUGGAUAUACUAUGCUAUCAUCUGUAUUCAAUAUAUAUGUAUAUUUGCUGGUACAUGCAUAAAACAUCUCAAGAAGUAUGCACCAAAUUCAUAAAACACUGAUUGCCCCUGGAAGGGCAACCAGGUAGUUGGGUGACAGGAGUGAGAGGGCCAAUUUUCACAGAAUAUUUAAUGCCCUAUUGUACCUUUUAAUUUUUAAGCCAUAUGAUUGUAUCACCUACUUAAAAAAAAAAUAAAUGUCCUUUCUGAGUUCUGUAUGUAUUUGCAUUUUCAGUGCAAUGAGCUAUAAGAGGCUGUACCUUACCAAAUUUAAGAGUUUUUAUUUUAAGAUUAAAAGGAUUUUUAAUAAAAAUUAUCAAAGGCAGCCGAGUGUUGAAACUGUUACUCUCAAGUUUUUAUCAUUUCCUCUAUAAAGUUGCUCAGACUUAGUUUCUGGCCUUAAAUCAUACCUAUUUUCAGCUUCCCUGAAAUCAAGAGUGUCCUGUGCCAUAUCAAUUAAAGUAAAUGUACUUUCAAUUAAAGGUGUUAAGUAUGAGUCUGAAAAGAUUAAUUCUUUAUAAAAAGAUGACCUUCAGUAGUUCGCUCCAAUUAGGCAUUUUUCCAACUAUAUUUCAUCUUGAUGGGACAAGUCUACUACUCACAAUCAAUCACUGUGAUCUUUUCAAAGGCGAGUAUUUUAGGUUCAGAGUCAUAAAAAGAAUGACUUGACUACGCAGCCUCCAUAACUUGAACCACAGGUGAUAUAGGCAGAGAUUAUGGGUGUUGGAUAUUACUUUUUGUGUUAUUAAUAUUUGAAGCAUCAGGAUAUGCAUAGUGAUAUUCUGGGUACAGUUCUUACACCUCUCUUCUCAUGACCUUACUAGAAUAAAUAUAUUUAAAUAAGACUGAUGGAAAGGAAGAGAGGAAAUGAACAAUGACACAAAUUAAUGUCCAACCAAAUUCCUCAUUUUUUUCCUGUCAUUUUAUUAUUAAACACAUUAUAAAUACUUGCUUUCCUCAUGGUUGUUUUGUUAUUGGACUACUUUAGUUUGAAGUGAAUCAUUGCUCAUAUACAGCACAUAAAACCAAGACUAUUAAGGAAAUGAAUGCUUGGUGAUUGUUUUAUGAGAACAUGCAAAAUCUUGGGGAAUAACAUUGCUUUCUCUUAAAAGUUAAAGGAAUUGAGCAUUUCUGUUUGUAUUUGGUACCUUCAGUAUGGAAUUAUUGGCCUUCACUCUGCCAUUCAUUAAAUUUGUAAACUUGGAGAAGCCAUUGAACACAGUCAUGGAAAAAAUGGAAAACAAAUAAUACCUCUUUGCAUAUCUCAAAG